GCCAGCCCCGCCAGCCCCGCGAUGGCUUGGGCCGCGCUCCUCGGCCUCCUGGCCGCACUGUUGCUGCUGCUGCUACUGAGCCGCCGCCGCACGCGGCGACCUGGUGAGCCUCCCCUGGACCUGGGCAGCAUCCCCUGGUUGGGGUAUGCCUUGGACUUUGGAAAAGAUGCUGCCAGCUUCCUCACGAGGAUGAAGGAGAAGCACGGUGACAUCUUUACUAUACUGGUUGGGGGCAGGUAUGUCACCGUUCUCCUGGACCCACACUCCUACGACGCGGUGGUGUGGGAGCCUCGCACCAGGCUCGACUUCCAUGCCUAUGCCAUCUUCCUCAUGGAGAGGAUUUUUGAUGUGCAGCUUCCACAUUACAGCCCCAGUGAUGAAAAGGCCAGGAUGAAACUGACUCUUCUCCACAGAGAGCUCCAGGCACUCACAGAAGCCAUGUAUACCAACCUCCAUGCAGUGCUGUUGGGCGAUGCUACAGAAGCAGGCAGUGGCUGGCACGAGAUGGGUCUCCUCGACUUCUCCUACAGCUUCCUGCUCAGAGCCGGCUACCUGACUCUUUACGGAAUUGAGGCGCUGCCACGCACCCAUGAAAGCCAGGCCCAGGACCGCGUCCACUCAGCUGAUGUCUUCCACACCUUUCGCCAGCUCGACCGGCUGCUCCCCAAACUGGCCCGUGGCUCCCUGUCAGUGGGCUGGAAUGCAAUGGUGCAAUCUUGGCUCACCACAACCUCCGCCCCCCAGAUUCAAGCGAUUCUCCUGCCUCAGCCUCCUGAGUAGCUGGGAUUACAGGCAUGCACCACCACACCCAGCUAAUUUUGUAUUUUUAGUAGAGACAGGGUUUCUCUGUGUUGGUCAUACUGGACUCGAACUCCCGACCUCAGGUGAUCCGCCCACGUCGGCCUUCCAAAGUGCUGGGAUUACAGGCGUGAGCCACCAUGCCUGGCCUGAUAAAGUUUAAUUUAUAAAUGAGGCACAGUAAGAGAUUAACAACAUAAUAAAAUGAAACCAAUUAUAACGAUAUACUGUAAUGAAAACAAAAUAAGGGUUACCUGAACACAAGUACUACCAUACCAUGACAGUUGACGUGAUAACUGAGACAGUGGCUCCCAAGUGACUAAUGGGCAGGUGUGGUCUACAGUGUGGAUACACCGGACAGAGGGAUGAUUCACCCCCCAGGCAAGAUGGAGCAGGAUGGCACAAGAGUUCAUCAUGCUACUCAGAAUGGUGUGCGAUUUCAAACUUAGGGAGUUUUUCAUUUAAUAUUCUUGGACCAUGGUUGACUAUGGGUGAUGGAAACCUUGGAAAGUGAAACUGGAUAAGACAGGACUGCUGUGUAUGUAAAUCCACGAAAGAAUGUUAUUCAGCCAUAAAAAGGGAGAAAUCCUGCCAUUUGUAACAAUAUAGAUGAACUUGGAAGACAAUAUUGUAAGUGAAAUAAGCCAGACACAGAAAAUCAAAUACCGCAUUAUGUCAUUUAUACGUGGGAGCUAAAAAAGUUGAAUUCAGAGGAACAGUAGAACAGUGGUUACCAGGGCUCAGGAGGUGGGGAAAUGGGGGUGUGUUGGUUGAGGGUAUAAACUUUGAGUUAUAAAAUGAAUAAGUUCUGGAGAUUUAAUAUACAAGUAUACAAUGUAUUGUAUACUUGAAAUUUGCUAAGAGAGUGGAUCUUAAGUAUUCUCACCAUGCAUGCACGUGUGAGUGUGCACCUAUGUAAGGUGAUGGAUAUGCUAAUUAGCUUGAUUGCAGCAAUCAUUUCACACCAUAUUUGUGUAUCAAAACAUCAUGUUGUACAACUUAAAUAAGAAUUUUCCUUUGUCAAUUAUACCUCAGCAAGGCUGGAAAAAAAUUAAGUAAUAACAGUGGUAAGUCUCCUUCCUUUUCUUGUCACAUCCCCUUCCACCAAUUCCCACUGCUCAUAAUUGAUUAGUUUUAUUAGUUUCAAAUGGAUCCUUCUAGAGUUCCUUCACACAAGUGCAAGUGAAUGUGACUAUAUUCUUAUUUUUCUUUUUUUCCACAAAUGCAUACUAAACACGUGGUUGCUGGCACUUUGCUUUGUGCUAACAAUAUAUCACAGCAAUAGAUAACUCUUGGGUAAGGUUUAGUGUGUCCUCUACACUGCUCUAAGGGAUAUACAAAUGUAAACUGAUUUGAUCCAUGAUCCAAUCACUGCUAUAUAUAUAUUUUUUUUGUUUUUGAGACAGAGUCUUGCUUGCUCUGUUGUCCAGCCUGGAGUGCAGUGGUGCAAUCUCCGCUCACUGCAACCUCUGCCUCCUGGGUUCAAGCGAUUCUCCUGCCCCAGCCUCCUGAGUAGCUGGGACUACAGGCGCCCACCACCAUGCUUGGCUAAUUUUUGUAUUUUUAUAUUUUUGUUAGAGAUGGGGUUUCACCAUGUUGGCCAGGCUGGUCUCGAACUCCUGACCUCAGGUGAUCUGCCCGUCUCGGCCUCCCCAAGUGCUGGGAUUACAGGAGUGAGCCACUGCACCCAGCCCACUGCUAUAUUUUUAUCCUGUGUUUUUUGCCAGGCAGGACAGAGCAGGAUGGCACAAGAUUUCAACACACUACUCAGAACAGCAUGUAAUUUAAAACUUAUGACUGUUUAUGUCCGGAAUUUUUCAUUUAAUAUUUUUGGACCAUGGUUGACCAUGGGUAACUGAAACCUUGGAAUUCAAAUUCUUUUGUAUUUUGAGUAUCACUCUGUCACCCAGGCUGGAGUGCAGUGGCUCCAUCUCAGCUCACUGCAACCUCCACCUCCCGGGUUCAAGUGAUUCUGCUGCCUCAGCCUCCCAAGUAACUGGGAUUACAGGUGCCUGCCACCACCCCCAGCUUAUCCUUUUUUGUAUUUUUAGUAGAGACGGGGUUUCACCAUGUUGGUCAGGCUGGCUUCAAACUCCUGAACUCAAGUGAUCUGCCCACCUUGGCCUCCCAAAGUGUUGGGAUUACAUGCGUGAGCCACUGCACCCGCCCAGAAUGCAAAUUCUUUGUUAUACAACACUAUCUUUGACUCAUUUUUGCCAAAUGACCUUCAUAUGCCUUUUAAAAAAAUUGUGGUAAAAUAAUAAAUAACAUAAAAUAUACUAUUUUAACCAUUUUAAUUGUAUAAUUCAGUGGCAGUAAAUACAUUCACAAUGUUGUAUAACCAUGCCGUUAUCUAUUUCCAGAAACUUUUCAUGAUUCUAAACAAAAGCUUUGUGCCCAUUAAACAAUAAUUCCCCACCUGCCUUUCCUCCCAGCCCGACAUAUCUUCUAUUCUACUUUCUGUCUCUUCUAUUCUACUUUCUAUUCUACUUUCUGUCGAAUAGUAUACUUCUAUUGUACUUUCUGUCUCUGAAUUUCCUGUUCUAGGAUUCUCAUUAUAUGAGAUUUUGGAGACAGAGUCUCUGUCGCCCAGGCUGGAGUGCAGUGUCGCCAUCUCAGCUCACUACAAUCUCCGCCUCCCGGGUUCAAGCUAUUCUUGUGCCUCAGCCUCCUGAGUAGCUGGGAUUACAGGUACACACCACCAUGCCUGGCUAAUUUUUUUUUUUUUUUUUUGUAUUUUAGUAGAGACAGGGUUUCACCAUGUUGCCCAUGCUGGUUCUCUAACUCCUGAGCCCAGGAAAUCUGCCCACCUUGGCCUCCCAAGGUGCUAGGAUUGCAGGCGUGAGCCACCAUGCCUGGCAUAUGCGUCAGAAUUUCAUUCCUUUUUAAGAGUGAAUACAUUGUGUGUAUAUACUGCAUUCUAUUUAUCCAUUCACCUAUCAACCGACAUUUGGGUUGUUUCUGCCUUUUGGCUACUGUGAAUAAUGCUGCUAUGAACAUUGGUGCACGAGUAUCUGUUUGAGUCUCUGGUUUCAGUUCUUUGGGCUAUAUACCUAGAACUAGAAUUACUGGAUCAUAUGGUAAUUCUUUAACUUUCUGAGGAACUGCUAAACUCUUUUUCACAGCAACUGCAGUAUUUUACAUUCCCACCAGCAAUGCAUAAGGGUUCCAAUUUCUCCACGUCCUCACCAUCACUUAUUUCCUAUGUUUUAAAUAGUAGCCAUCCUCAUGGUUGUGAAUGGUAUCACACUGUGGUUUUUACAUGCAUUUUCUAAUGACUAAUGGUGUUGAGCAUUGUUUCAUGUGUUUAUCAGCCAUUUGUAUCUCUUCUUUGGAGAAAUAUCUAUUCAAGUCCUUUGCCAAUUUUCAAAUCAGGUUGUUUGUUUUUUAUUGUUGUUGAGUCGUAGGAGUUCUUUUAUAUAUUUUGGGUGUUAGACCCUUAUCAGAUAUAUUAUUUACAAAUAUUUUCUCACUUUCUGUCAGCUGUCUUUUCAUACUGCAUUACCUUUUUUGCUUAAUUAUUCAUUGAUUGUGCAAAUAUAGAGUGCCUCCUAUGUACUCAGAACUGCUGUAGGCACAGGGGAAAAGUGGAGAAUGGUCCUGCCUUGCUUUUUAAAGUCAUCUGUAAACGCCGUGUUUACAGUGAUAUUCAAGAUUGCAGUUGUGUGGUCAGACUUCAAAGAAUGCCAGUUAUUUCUAAAGCUGUGUUAAAUUUCUUUGCCUCUUUUUUUAGCCAUCCCAUCAGAUGAUGCUUAGAAGUAUCCAGAGUUGGCAUCAACUGAGGUGGUUUCAACACUGCCCGCGCCCUGCAGGCCUAAACCUCUGGAUGCCCAGUUCCCACGCACGUGAUUUUGACAUGAUCAAUCUGGGGUUGGCACCUGGGCAUCCAGAGAUUUAAGAGCUCCCAGGUAAUUCUUCAGAGAGCCUGAAAAGUGGAGAAACAUAGGAAGAUAAUGUAUUUCAGUUGAACACUUAAGCUUAUUGCUUUACAUUGAAAUGUCACCCGAAAUGGUGACAUUCAUUUCAAUGUAAAACAAUGAGCUCAAGUUGAAGUCUAAAAGUUAAACAUAUUCAGCGUAUUAUUUGAAAAUGAAGCCAACAUACUUUAAAAAAAAAACAUAGUCUACAUUUUCGACCCUUUCAAAUGCCCUGUGAGGUGCAGCCAGGUUUAGAAUCGCUGGUGGGGCGAGUCUUCCUGAAACACGGCUUGUGGUUCAGAAGAGUCAGUGAGGGAGUUUCCAAUACUUUGAAACUUCAGAGCAAUCCAAAAUGACUCUCACUUUUCCAAGGGGUGAUUUCGGAGAAAACCAAAUUUUAUAUUUUAUAUUUUUGUUUUAAACUUUAUAUUUGUGCAUAUAAAUAGCAUUACCGUGGAGCUUUAAAACAAUGUAUAUUAAGGCUCAUGUAUGGUUCAUGAAAAUAUUUUAAAAAAAAAAAAAGAAGUAGAAAAGAAAACAAUAUCUAAAUAGUGUCAUUCUUCAGUGCCCGGCUUUAUCCCCUUACCAGUCUGCCCUUGGGAACUCUCUGUGUCUGUAGGUAAAAUGUACUAACUCACUUUCACUGCUGUAUGUUUCCAGAACAUAAACACACCAUUGUCUGUUUAAUGGUGAUGCACGCUAGUGAUCUGUGGGCCAAAGUUGACCUUCAGAGAUGCUUCUGUGGUCUGCACAGUGAUUAAAAACUUUUUACUUGGAUGCUAACCUUAAAAAACAUCAGAAGGUUAUACAUAAUUGUCUGGAUUAUCAGCUUCCUUUGAAAGCACAGGCCUUCUGGCCAUGCUGGGGUGUUUCCCUCUCCUGCCGAGGGCUGGUUGGUGGGCUAAGUGCCAUGGCCCCUUUCUGGCCCGUCUCUCUUUUACUUGGCCUGCCUUCUCUGGAGUGAGUUGAGUUUGAGACUCCAGCCCAAUCUGCCAGUUAGGUUGUUGCUGAUGUCUUUCUGUGAUUGCUGCUGUGCUGAGCCUGCUCACAGUGGCCUCCUCCUCAUGCACAUGGGCUGGCAUUGCUCUGGGGUUGGACCCUGGGGAGGGAGAAUGCUGCUCAGUGUUUAGUGUUCCUUCUCCUGCUCUGGAAAGAACUACCAUUUAUUUAAUGCAUGAUAUAGUUUUGCUGUGUCCCCACCCAAAUCUCAUCUUGAACUGUAGCUCCCAUAAUUCUCAUGUGUUGUGGGAGGGAC